AUAGGAGUGAGCCACGCCCGGGCUGUGGGAAUAAGAUGGCGGGGAAGAAGAAUGUUCUGUCGUCUCUCGCAGUUUACGCGGAAGAUUCAGAGCCCGAGUCUGAUGGCGAGGCUGGAAUCGAGGCGGUGGGCAGCGCGGCUGGAAGAUGACGAUUCAGAGACUGAAAAACCUGAGGCUGAUGACCCAAAGGAGAAGCUCGGCACAGUGACAGAGGCACCCAGGGCUCAGCAAGCUCAUGGCCCAGCUUGUUGGACUCAGAGGGCAGAAGAAUCACAUUCUAAACAUGAUAAGAGACGUGACUCAACAACCUCAGCUGAGCCUGGCAGCACACACACCCCACACUCCUUUCCAUCUCCAGGUUCACAAAAGCCACAAGAAGCCACGGGGAGGCUCCUGGCCUCUUACUUUACCUAAGGAGGCCCUGAAGUGGCAAGAUAAUACAGAAGCAGAAAAGCGAGACCCCCAGGAACUCGUGGCCUCCUUUUCUGAAAGAGUUCGGAACAUGUCGCCUGAUGAAAUCAAGAUCCCGCCAGAACCCCCUGGCAGAUGUUCAAAUCACUUGCAAGACAAGAUCCAGAAGCUUUAUGAACGAAAGAUAAAGGAGGGAAUGGAUAUGAACUACAUUAUCCAAAGGAAGAAAGAAUUUCGGAACCCUAGCAUCUACGAGAAGCUGAUCCAGUUCUGUGCCAUUGACGAGCUUGGCACCAACUACCCAAAGGAUAUGUUUGAUCCCCAUGGCUGGUCUGAGGACUCCUACUAUGAGGCAUUAGCCAAGGCCCAGAAAAUUGAGAUGGACAAAUUGGAAAAGGCCAAAAAGGAGCGAACAAAAGCUUGUUGCAGGGACGUGUCUGCAGCGCCUGGGGACCGGAGCUGUCCUUCCCCUGUGCGGGCGGGCACCGCCUCCUCCUGGAUUGAGUUUGUGACGGGCACCAAAAAAGGCACCACGACCAACGCCACGUCCACCACCACUACCACUGCCAGCACAGCUGUUGCAGAUGCUCAGAAGAGAAAGAGCAAGUGGGAUUCGGCUAUCCCAGUGACAACGAUAGCCCAGCCCACCAUCCUCACCACCACAGCCACCCUGCCAGCUGUUGUCACGGUCACCACCAGCGCCAGCGGCUCCAAGACCACCGUCAUCUCUGCUGUGGGCACCAUUGUGAAGAAGGCCAAGCAGUGACCUGAGGGGCCACCCUAGGACUUGAAAGGACCGUGCAGCCCAGUGACCACUGCCCAGUGGGAGGCGCCACUUUGUAUAUUUCAGGACUGGGACCUACUCCCCAGAUGCCACCUGAGAGGAGCUUCUGUUUGGCAUUCCAGAUGGAAGGACAGGCAGCACGGGAGCCAGGCGCUGUGGACAGGGUCUGUCCACGCACCACCUGGGGUCUGCCGCCUAUUAAAAGUGCCGUAUUCUUACCUCUUGGCAUCUCAGAUGCACUGGCCUCUCCUGCAUUCUGUUUGCAGGCAAAUGCUUCAGCUCACAUGUCCCCCAAGACUCAAUAGUCUUGGUUGGGACUAUUGCCUCAGGGUUGACAACAGGGUGAUGGAGGCCUGGGACGCUGUUCAGAGGGGUGACCCAAGAAGUCACCGUUGUUAUCCGUGUAUGCCUCUGGGCAUGGACAGGCGGGAGUCCCCGAGCCCCACGUAUGCCCCAUCUGCCGCCUUGAUCCCAAAACCCAGCCAGUUCUCGGGUGAUGGUGGAGCUGUGCUCCCUUGAGUGCACUUGAGCACUCCCCAGACCAGAUCACUUUUUGGACACACCCAGGAAGGCUUUUGAAGUCAAGCCAGUUUCCAGAAGGGCUGGGGUGAGAUCCUGACCUGUGCAGAGAGUGGGGAGGCGUCAGCGCCUGGCCAGGGCUGCCCCAGUCCUUUGGUGCCCGGUGAGCGCAGCCAGCAGGAGCUGAGCAGCGGGGGAGAUGAAUCACCUCCUGCCUUGGCGAGGCGGCAGCUCAUUGUUUACAGGCAAGCCCUGCUCCUGGGAGGGCUCCUGCCACCCCACCCUUCCUCUGUGUGUUAUCUCUGCCCCACAGCAGCCCCUGGGCAGCACCAGUGGCCACUGGGCUCCCCCCGGGGUUGAAACGGGUUUCCCAGACCAGGGGUUCAGAGGAGACUAUUUACCCUUCAUGAUCUUUGGCGAUUCUCCACUGGAGCGGAAGGGCUGUGUGUCAAAAGAAGGAAGCCAGGCUGUGAAGGGCCGUGUUGCUUUCAGUGGGUGGGCAGAGGUUUAGAAAGGUGGUUCUGAAAUGGCACCUGGUACUCUUGUGGGACCUGGGGAAUAUAAGGAACUCUGUGCAUGAGGUUUCAAAAAUAAAAAUUGAGUCCACUCUCCCCGUACACACACACUCGGGCACUUCAGGAGGUCAGUUCUCACCCCUUCCUCGAUGGGGCUUUAAAGCUCUGGGGAGAAGAGCUGCUCCCCACUCAUGCCCCAGAGGGACUGUGAAAAGGCUUCCUGUGACCUCCGAUGGCGGCCCCUCAUUGGCCAAGGGCACUGUGGAUGUUUUGUGGGAGGCAGCAUGGCACCGUGGAAAGGGCAGUAGACGUGGAGCCGGCACCUCUGGUCUGGAUUCCACUUAAAACCAGUUGAGUGGUCUCAAGCCCUUAACCUCUGUAAGCCUGUUUCUUCUCUGAAAUCACAGUAAUAAAGCGUCGUAAGAUGGUUGGGAAGAACCAGAGGUGACUUAUGCAAAAGCUUUAUAAACUGUAAAGUUCCUGCCA